AUUUGUGGUGAGAUUCUCUCCCAGGCCACAAGACAUUUCCUGCUCGGAACCUUGUUUACUAAUUUCCACUGCUUUUAAGGCCCUGCACUGAAAAUGCAAGCUCAGGCGCCGGUGGUCGUUGUGACCCAACCUGGAGUCGGUCCCGGUCCGGCCCCCCAGAACUCCAACUGGCAGACAGGCAUGUGUGACUGUUUCAGCGACUGCGGAGUCUGUCUCUGUGGCACAUUUUGUUUCCCGUGCCUUGGGUGUCAAGUUGCAGCUGAUAUGAAUGAAUGCUGUCUGUGUGGAACAAGCGUCGCAAUGAGGACUCUCUACAGGACCCGAUAUGGCAUCCCUGGAUCUAUUUGUGAUGACUAUAUGGCAACUCUUUGCUGUCCUCAUUGUACUCUUUGCCAAAUCAAGAGAGAUAUCAACAGAAGGAGAGCCAUGCGUACUUUCUAAAAACUGAUGGUGAGUCAAUGCAAACAUGCCUCUCAGAACAUGUGGGUUUUUAGAAAUAUCACUAAAGACUUUGUCAAUUAUUUGUUGUUUUGAAUAAUUCAGCAAUAACUAUUUCUUAAGUCUCCUGAAGUGCUAUCAUAAUAUCAAGAUUGGCUUUAAUUUUCUUCUUAUGAAGAAGAUAGCUCUAUACUUUGAAACCAUAUUUUAGUAAAUAAAGGAAUGGUGAAUUUUCUAAACUUCUCAGAAUUCUGGUGAUCUAUUAAGGAAGCACUUACCACUUGUAAAAUACCAGAGUAUGGUGAGAUACAAAAGAAUUAGAAAACAUGUUCCCUGCUAAGACAAACAAGUUGACAAAAGGAAUUCGUAAAUAAUUAUAAAAUAGAAGAGUAAAGAAAAUAACAUUCUGUAUGAUAUUUGGAUUGAUUGUGGCAUAAAGCAUCUAUCAUAGCAAGGUGAGGUUAAAUAGAAAACUCCUGUUGGAGAAGCUGAACUUUGAAAGAGGUGAACAUAGAAUUUAGAAUGUUUGGAAAUGUUAUAUAGAAUUAACCAUCUGAAAUUCAAUCAAGUCAUUUUCAACUAAUUUUUCUCAGGACUAUCUAUUGAGGAUGUAGUUAAGUAGAAAUCAACAUGACUUACUCCAUCCCCUGUAGAAUAUAUAUUAAGUAUGGGAAGAACACAAUUUUUCUACUCUUUGUAAUAUCCAGUUUCCUUCCUGAAGUGAUAAGGACUCUGUAUGGGUUAAUAAAAAUAACUCUUGGGAGAUACGUAAAAAAAUGUUCAUUUACUUAGCAAGUAAUGUAUUAAGGAUCUAGGAUCAAGUAUAUAUUAUCUUAGCAACUAAUGUAUCAAUGUAUCAAUAUCUAAGACUAGGUAAGAUACUGUUAGGUAUUGUAGUAGGGUUGGGGAGCAAGAUAAAUAAGCUAGUCCCUCUGUCAUUAUAGAAUUUAUACGAAAAAGGGGGAUUAGACAAACCCCUAACUAAAAUGCAGAAUUCAAUUAAUGCCUAUAGACAAAGCGGUAUUUUAUGUUCAGAGGAGGAAAAGAUCACAUCUUGUAAGAUGUAUAGGUGAAAGUUUCUUGAAAGCAGUGAUUUUUAAUUCUAAAGGGGAAGUGCGUAUUAGUUCUCAACAAGAAACAGAUGGCACUCAAACUGUGAUAGUUCAAAGAUUUAAUGAAGACUAAUUAUAAAGGUGUGGGUGGGGCAUUGUAGGGAGAUGACAAGGGAUGGCAUAAUAACCUGCCUGGCAACAGCCCCAGGGAGGAGAAGAGGGAGCAGUGACCUGAAUCCUUAAGGAGAGAGCUGUGUGAAGAGGCCUGCCCUGAAAGAAACAGUAUCCUCUCAAGAGAGGGUUGUGAGCAGCCCGAGGCAACCCAUAGAACUGAAAAAGUACCCUGACCUCACUUUCGGAUGUCCUUCUGGUUUUCCCAUUGGCUGAACCCACCAGAAAGGCAGAGGGCAGCAAAGUGUCACGGUAGUCCGCAGGUCGCUUCCCAGGGCACACAGCAGGAUGGUCAAGGGAGUAAGUAAAUCAGAUAGGGGCAAACAGAGGAUCACUGACUCAAGAUGUGGUUUUAAUUAAUAGAAAUGGAGGCUGAGUGCAGUGGCUCACACCUGUGAUCCCAGCACUUUGGGAGGCCAAGGCAAGAGGACUGCUUGAACCCAGGAGUUCAAGACCAGCCUGGGGAACAUGUUGAAACCCUGUCUCUUGAAAAAAUACAAAAAUUAGCUAGGUGUGGUGGUGCACGCCUGUAGUCCCAGAUACUUGGGAGGCUGAGGUGGGAGGAUCACUUGAGCCUGGGAGGUAGAAGCUGCAGUGAGCUAUGAU